ACUCUUGUCAGGGCCGCGGCACAUGGGCGGCCGGAUGCGCUGAGCCCGGCGCUGCGGGGCCGCGGAGCGCUGGGGAGCAGCGGCCGCCGGCGCGGGGAGGGGGGUGGGGUGGGACGGCGCACCGCCUCCGGUGCUGGCACUAGGGGCUGGGGUCGGCGCGGUGUCUUCUGCCCUUCUGCAGCCGUCGACAUUUUUUUUUCUUUCUUUUUUUCAAUUUUGAACAUUUUGCAAAACGAGGGGUUCGAGGCAGGUGAGAGCAUCCUGCACGUCGCCGGGGAGCCCGCGGGCACUUGGCGCGCUCUCCUGGGACCGUCUGCACUGGAAACCCGAAAGUUUUUUUUUAAUAUAUAUUUUUAUGCAGAUGUAUUUAUAAAGAUAUAAGUAAUUUUUUUCUUCCCUUUUCUCCACCGCCUUGAGAGCGAGUACUUUUGGCAAAGGACGGAGGAAAAGCUCAGCAACAUUUUAGGGGGCGGUUGUUUCUUUCUUAUUUCUUUUUUUAAGGGGAAAAAAUUUGAGUGCAUCGCGAUGGAGAAAAUGUCCCGACCGCUCCCCCUGAAUCCCACCUUUAUCCCGCCUCCCUACGGCGUGCUCAGGUCCCUGCUGGAGAACCCGCUGAAGCUCCCCCUUCACCACGAAGACGCAUUUAGUAAAGAUAAAGACAAGGAAAAGAAGCUGGAUGAUGAGAGUAACAGCCCGACGGUCCCCCAGUCGGCAUUCCUGGGGCCUACCUUAUGGGACAAAACCCUUCCCUAUGACGGAGAUACUUUCCAGUUGGAAUACAUGGACCUGGAGGAGUUUUUGUCAGAAAAUGGCAUUCCCCCCAGCCCAUCUCAGCAUGACCACAGCCCUCACCCUCCUGGGCUGCAGCCAGCUUCCUCGGCUGCCCCCUCGGUCAUGGACCUCAGCAGCCGGGCCUCUGCACCCCUUCACCCUGGCAUCCCAUCUCCGAACUGUAUGCAGAGCCCCAUCAGACCAGGUCAGCUGUUGCCAGCAAACCGCAAUACACCAAGUCCCAUUGAUCCUGACACCAUCCAGGUCCCAGUGGGUUAUGAGCCAGACCCAGCAGAUCUUGCCCUUUCCAGCAUCCCUGGCCAGGAAAUGUUUGACCCUCGCAAACGCAAGUUCUCUGAGGAAGAACUGAAGCCACAGCCCAUGAUCAAGAAAGCUCGCAAAGUCUUCAUCCCUGAUGACCUGAAGGAUGACAAGUACUGGGCAAGGCGCAGAAAGAACAACAUGGCAGCCAAGCGCUCCCGCGACGCCCGGAGGCUGAAAGAGAACCAGAUCGCCAUCCGGGCCUCGUUCCUGGAGAAGGAGAACUCGGCCCUCCGCCAGGAGGUGGCUGACUUGAGGAAGGAGCUGGGCAAAUGCAAGAACAUACUUGCCAAGUAUGAGGCCAGGCACGGGCCCCUGUAGGAUGGCAUUUUUGCAGGCUGGCUUUGGAAUAGAUGGACAGUUUGUUUCCUGUCUGAUAGCACCACACGCAAACCAACCUUUCUGACAUCAGCACUUUACCAGAGGCAUAAACACAACUGACUCCCAUUUUGGUGUGCAUCUGUGUGUGUGUGCGUGUAUAUGUGCUUGUGCUCAUGUGUGUGGUCAGCGGUAUGUGCGUGUGCGUGUUCCUUUGCUCUUGCCAUUUUAAGGUAGCCCUCUCAUCGUCUUUUAGUUCCAACAAAGAAAGGUGCCAUGUCUUUACUAGACUGAGGAGCCCUCUCGCGGGUCUCCCAUCCCCUCCCUCCUUCACUCCUGCCUCCUCAGCUUUGCUUCAUGUUCGAGCUUACCUACUCUUCCAGGACUCUCUGCUUGGAUUCACUAAAAAGGGCCCUGGUAAAAUAGUGGAUCUCAGUUUUUAAGAGUACAAGCUCUUGUUUCUGUUUAGUCCGUAAGUUACCAUGCUAAUGAGGUGCACACAAUAACUUAGCACUACUCCGCAGCUCUAGUCCUUUAUAAGUUGCUUUCCUCUUACUUUCAGUUUUGGUGAUAAUCGUCUUCAAAUUAAAGUGCUGUUUAGAUUUAUUAGAUCCCAUAUUUACUUACUGCUAUCUACUAAGUUUCCUUUUAAUUCUACCAACCCCAGAUAAGUAAGAGUACUAUUAAUAGAACACAGAGUGUGUUUUUGCACUGUCUGUACCUAAAGCAAUAAUCCUAUUGUACGCUAGAGCAUGCUGCCUGAGUAUUACUAGUGGACGUAGGAUAUUUUCCCUACCUAAGAAUUUCACUGUCUUUUAAAAAACAAAAAGUAAAGUAAUGCAUUUGAGCAUGGCCAGACUAUUCCCUAGGACAAGGAAGCAGAGGGAAAUGGGAGGUCUAAGGAUGAGGGGUUAAUUUAUCAGUACAUGAGCCAAAAACUGCGUCUUGGAUUAGCCUUUGACAUUGAUGUGUUCGGUUUUGUUGUUCCCCUUCCCUCACACCCUGCCUCGCCCCCACUUUUCUAGUUAACUUUUUCCAUAUCCCUCUUGACAUUCAAAACAGUUACUUAAGAUUCAGUUUUCCCACUUUUUGGUAAUAUAUAUAUUUUUGUGAAUUAUACUUUGUUGUUUUUAAAAAGAAAAUCAGUUGAUUAAGUUAAUAAGUUGAUGUUUUCUAAGGCCCUUUUUCCUAGUGGUGUCAUUUUUGAAUGCCUCAUAAAUUAAUGAUUCUGAAGCUUAUGUUUCUUAUUCUCUGUUUGCUUUUGAACGUAUGUGCUCUUAUAAAGUGGACUUCUGAAAAAUGAAUGUAAAAGACACUGGUGUAUCUCAGAAGGGGAUGGUGUUGUCACAAACUGUGGUUAAUCCAAUCAAUUUAAAUGUUUACUAUAGACCAAAAGGAGAGAUUAUUAAAUCGUUUAAUGUUUAUACAGAGUAAUUAUAGGAAGUUCUUUUUUGUACAGUAUUUUUCAGAUAUAAAUACUGACAAUGUAUUUUGGAAGACAUAUAUUAUAUAUAGAAAAGAGGAGAGGAAAACUAUUCCAUGUUUUAAAAUUAUAUAGCAAAGAUAUAUAUUCACCAAUGUUGUACAGAGAAGAAGUGCUUGGGGGUUUUUGAAGUCUUUAAUAUUUUAAGCCCUAUCACUGACACAUCAGCAUGUUUUCUGCUUUAAAUUAAAAUUUUAUGACAGUAUCGAGGCUUGUGAUGACGAAUCCUGCUCUAAAAUACACAAGGAGCUUUCUUGUUUCUUAUUAGGCCUCAGAAAGAAGUCAGUUAACGUCACCCAAAAGCACAAAAUGGAUUUUAGUCAAAUAUUUAUUGGAUGAUACAGUGUUUUUUAGGAAAAGCAUCUGCCACAAAAAUGUUCACUUCGAAAUUCUGAGUUCCUGGAAUGGCACGUUGCUGCCAGUGCCCCAGACAGUUCUUUUCUACCCUGCGGGCCCGCACGUUUUAUGAGGUUGAUAUCGGUGCUAUGUGUUUGGUUUAUAAUUUGAUAGAUGUUUGACUUUAAAGAUGAUUGUUCUUUUGUUUCAUUAAGUUGUAAAAUGUCAAGAAAUUCUGCUGUUACGACAAAGAAACAUUUUACGCUAGAUUAAAAUAUCCUUUCAUCAAUGGGAUUUUCUAGUUUCCUGCCUUCAGAGUAUCUAAUCCUUUAAUGAUCUGGUGGUCUCCUCGUCAAUCCAUCAGCAAUGCUUCUCUCAUAGUGUCAUAGACUUGGGAAACCCAACCAGUAGGAUAUUUCUACAAGGUGUUCAUUUUGUCACAAGCUGUAGAUAACAGCAAGAGAUGGGGGUGUAUUGGAAUUGCAAUACAUUGUUCAGGUGAAUAAUAAAAUCAAAAACUUUUGCAAUCUUAAGCAGAGAUAAAUAAAAGAUAGCAAUAUGAGACACAGGUGGACGUAGAGUUGGCCUUUUUACAGGCAAAGAGGCGAAUUGUAGAAUUGUUAGAUGGCAAUAGUCAUUAAAAACAUAGAAAAAUGAUGUCUUUAAGUGGAGAAUUGUGGAAGGAUUGUAACAUGGACCAUCCAAAUUUAUGGCCGUAUCAAAUGGUAGCUGAAAAAACUAUAUUUGAGCACUGGUCUCUCUUGGAAUUAGAUGUUUAUAUCAAAUGAGCAUCUCAAAUGUUUUCUGCAGAAAAAAAUAAAAAGAUUCUAAUAAAAUGUAUUCUCUUGUGUGCCAGGAGAGGUUUCAGAAACCUACCUCGUCUUACAAAUUUAAACACUUUGGAGUCUGUACAGGUGCCUUAUAUGUAGGUCAUUGUCACGAUACACACACACGAACACUCCCUCUGGACUGGCUGCCUCUCCAUCCAGGGCAGUUAACUAGCAAACAAGGCAGAUCUGCUUCAUGGAGCGGGAGGCCAUGGCUUGACUCUGAGUGAUUUGGGUCAACCGGAGUCAGACGCAUGUCUGCACGCUGCAGCUAUUAUGAGAGUCCCUUUGUCAUUUUUCACCUUUUCAUCCUAAGCAUCUUUCAGAGAUUAAUUAUUUGGCCAUUAACAAUGAAUCCAAAUCAUAUCAUACUGACAUCAUCUAGACAUGAUUUGGAAGGAACAGCUUAGGACCUCCUGAUGAGGUCACAUUGUUGUUUCUUUUAACUAGACUUGGCAAAGAAAGGCAAAAAUUGACCAGCCUAUCUUUCUGCUGGUGCUGCCUUAAGGAGGUAGUUUGUUGAGGGGAGGGCUGUAGAUCAUUACUUCUUUCUCUUCAGGAAGUGGCCACUUUGAACCAUUCAAAUACCACAUUAGGCAAGACUGUGAUAGGCCUUUUGUCUUCAAAUACAACAGGCCUCCACUGACCCAUCCCUCAAAGCAGAAGGACCCUUUGAGGAGAGUACAGAUGGGAUUCCACAGUGGGGUGGGUGGAAUGGAAACCUGUACUAGACCACCCAGAGGUUCCUUCUAACCCACUGGUUUGGUGGGGAACUCACAGUAAUUCCAAAUGUACAAUCAGAUGUCUAGGGUCUGUUUUCGGAAGAAGCAAGAAUUAUCAGUGGCACCCUCCCCACUGCCCCCAGUGUAAAACAAUAGACAUUCUGUGAAAUGCAAAGCUAUUCUUUGGUUUUUCUAGUAGUUUAUCUCAUUUUACCCUAUUCUUCCUUUAAGGAAAACUCAAUCUUUAUCACAGUCAAUUAGAGCGAUCCCAAGGCAUGGGACCAGGCCUGCUUGCCUAUGUGUGAUGGCAAUUGGAGAUCUGGAUUUAGCACUGGGGUCUCAGCACCCUGCAGGUGUCUGAGACUAAGUGAUCUGCCCUCCAGGUGGCGAUCACCUUCUGCUCCUAGGUACCCCCACUGGCAAGGCCAAGGUCUCCUCCACGUUUUUUCUGCAAUUAAUAAUGUCAUUUAAAAAAUGAGCAAAGCCUUAUCCGAAUCGGAUAUAGCAACUAAAGUCAAUACAUUUUGCAGGAGGCUAAGUGUAAGAGUGUGUGUGUGUGUGUGUGCGUGCAUGUGUGUGUGUGUGUAUGUGUGUGAAUAAGUCGACAUAAAGUCUUUAAUUUUGAGCACCUUACCAAACAUAACAAUAAUCCAUUAUCCUUUUGGCAACACCACAAAGAUCGCAUCUGUUAAACAGGUACAAGUUGACAUGAGGUUAGUUUAAUUGUACACCAUGAUAUUGGUGGUAUUUAUGCUGUUAAGUCCAAACCUUUAUCUGUCUGUUAUUCUUAAUGUUGAAUAAACUUUGAAUUUUUUCCUUUCUUUCAUGUAUUUUUAUUAACAGUUGGCUAGCAAUGGUAUUCUGUUCCCACCUCGGUAGCAAAGAGACCAUUUGUAGAGAUUAUUACCUAGAUAAUAAAAUGAUAAUACUAUAUAAUUAGUAA